GCCAUUGGCCUCGGCUCCGGGCCCGCUGCCGGCGUGUGGGCGAGGCUCGGGGCGCGAGGACCGAGCAGGGCGGUGGGUUCGCGAGCCGGGGGGAGGGGCCGGGGCGGUGGCGGCUGUGGCCGGUACUGGACCCGGCGGGAUGAGCGAGGUGGAGGCGGCAGCGGGGGCUACAGCGGUCCCCGCGGCGACGGUGCCCGCGACGGCGGCAGGGGUGGUAGCGGUGGUGGUACCGGUGCCCGCAGGGGAGCCGCAGAAAGGCGGCGGGGCGGGCGGCGGGGGCGGAGCCGCCUCGGGCCCCGCUGCUGGGACCCCCUCGGCGCCGGGCUCCCGCACCCCUGGCAAUCCGGCGACGGCGGUCUCGGGAACCCCCGCCCCCCCGGCCCGGAGUCAGGCGGACAAGCCGGUGCUGGCAAUCCAAGUCCUGGGCACUGUCAAAUGGUUCAACGUCCGGAAUGGUUACGGAUUCAUCAACAGGAAUGACACCAAGGAAGAUGUCUUUGUUCACCAGCUUGAGAACCACUGCUUGGUGGAAAGAGCUCUCACUGGGACUGAGACAGCUAUUAAAAGAAACAACCCCAGGAAGUUUCUGCGCAGCGUUGGAGAUGGGGAGACUGUGGAAUUUGAUGUCGUGGAAGGAGAGAAGGGCGCAGAAGCCACUAAUGUAACUGGGCCUGGGGGAGUACCCGUGAAGGGCAGCCGUUAUGCCCCCAACCGACGUAAGUCCCGCCGAUUCAUCCCCCGGCCUCCCUCAGUUGCCCCACCACCCAUGGUGGCAGAGAUCCCCUCGGCGGGGACAGGACCUGGCAGUAAAGGGGAGCGGGCUGAAGACUCUGGGCAACGGCCCCGACGAUGGUGCCCCCCACCCUUCUUCUACCGACGGCGGUUUGUGCGAGGCCCCCGGCCUCCCAACCAGCAGCAGCCUAUAGAGGGCACUGACAGGGUAGAACCCAAAGAGACAGCCCCAUUGGAGGGGCACCAACAGCAGGGAGAUGAGCGAGUCCCCCCGCCCAGAUUCCGGCCCAGGUACCGAAGGCCUUUCCGCCCCAGGCCACGCCAGCAGCCUACCACAGAAGGUGGGGAUGGUGAGACCAAGCCCAGCCAAGGUCCCGCUGAUGGUUCCCGGCCUGAGCCCCAGCGCCCACGAAACCGCCCCUACUUCCAGCGGAGACGGCAGCAGGCCCCUGGCCCCCAGCAGGCCCCUGGCCCCCGGCAGCCCGCAGCCCCUGAGACCUCAGCCCCUGUCAACAGUGGGGACCCCACCACCACCAUCCUGGAGUGAUUCCAACUCAACUCAGAGGACACCCAGAGCUGCCAUCUGGUAUCUGCCAGUUUUUCCAAAUGACCUGUACCCUACCCAGUACCCUGCUCCCCCUUUCCCAUAAUUCAUGACAUCAAAACACCAGCUUUUCACCUUUUCCUUGAGACUCAGGAGGACCAAAGCAGCAGCCUUUUGCUUUUUCUUUUUUCUUCCCUCCCCUUAUCAAGGGUUGAAGGAAGGGAGCCAUCCUUACUGUUCAGAGACAGCAACUCCCUCCCGUAACUCAGGCUGAGAAGGAACCAGCCAGCUCUUACCUCCUCCUGGUUGCUUUUCUUGCCCCCACCCCAAGUUUAUUUUUGUUUUCCCCCGGCCCCCUACCUCUGAAGCCAUUUUAUGAUCUGUCAUGUGCCACCUGAGCCUCCAGUAAAAACAAAAACAGGC